AGAAUCAUCAGCCUUUUCAUUGGAAACCAUGGAAGGACGGUUCUGGGAAAAUAAUGAAAAUCAUACCACACCAUAGAGACAACCAGAAGCCCUGCUCAGAUGACAGAGUUCUCCUCGCCUUCCAGAAAAUGCCCCCGCUUCCGCUGGAGAAUGGAAAUUGGCAAAGAGAGACGGAAAAGCUCCAAUUUGCGCCUUUGCUAUUUUAGGAGAGGUUGAAAUUACGAGCCAAAGUGGAGUGAUGCGCUAAGCGGAGUGACCUCCGUACUCCAAGAAAAGAGAAAACCCAGGUUCUCUGCUUGUGAAGUGGCUCGAGCUCUUAGGCGUGAGGCAUUAUUAUAUAAAUUCAAGCUCGCUCGUGAUCCUUAGUACCCUGAGUUGCCUGAAGGGGGGAAUGGCACUGCCUGCGUGUGCAGUCCGGGAGUUCGAGCCGCCGCGGCAACCGGAGCGAGGAGCGCCCGUCCGCACCACCUGUCCCCGCCGGCAUUCCAGAGUAGAGGCCGAAUUGGCAGCGAGCCGGCCCGGGUCGGUCGCCGCCUCAGUUCGCGCGGGCCCUCCUAGGGGUGUGUCUCACGGAUUCCACACCCGGCCGCUCCUGGACAAGCCCCGAAAGGCGUCUUCUUCCCUGGCGGGAGCCGCGUGCGCCCCGCUUUUCGCGCUGCUGUCCCGGGGCCGCCGCAGGCGGAUGCACGUCCUCAGGCGACGCUGGGACCUGGGCUCCCUCUGCCGGGCCCUGCUCACUCGGGGCCUGGCCGCCCUGGGCCACUCGCUGAAGCACGUGCUCGGUGCGAUCUUCUCCAAGAUUUUCGGCCCCAUGGCCAGCGUCGGGAACAUGGAUGAGAAAUCCAACAAGCUGCUGCUAGCUUUGGUGAUGCUCUUCCUAUUUGCCGUGAUCGUCCUCCAAUACGUGUGCCCCGGCACAGAAUGCCAGCUCCUCCGCCUGCAGGCGUUCAGCUCCCCGGUGCCGGACCCGUACCGCUCGGAGGAUGAGAGCUCCGCCAGGUUCGUGCCCCGCUACAAUUUCACCCGCGGCGACCUCCUGCGCAAGGUAGACUUCGACAUCAAGGGCGAUGACCUGAUCGUGUUCCUGCACAUCCAGAAGACCGGGGGCACCACUUUCGGCCGCCACUUGGUGCGUAACAUCCAGCUGGAGCAGCCGUGCGAGUGCCGCGUGGGUCAGAAGAAAUGCACUUGCCACCGGCCGGGUAAGCGGGAAACCUGGCUCUUCUCCAGGUUCUCCACGGGCUGGAGCUGCGGGUUGCACGCCGACUGGACCGAGCUCACCAGCUGUGUGCCCUCCGUGGUGGACGGCAAGCGCGACGCCAGGCUGAGACCGUCCAGCCUGCAGCAGAAUCACCUGGCGAGGAGGUGCCUGUUGAAAAAGAUAAGAAGUUUCAUUCAGAAAAGAUGACCCUGAAGUAAGUCUUCUCACUCAUUUCUAUUUAUUCACAGUUCCUACUUUACUAAGAAAGUUUUUAAUUAUUGGCCAUUAUCCGUGACUGAAAAUACAUUAAGUAAAGUUGCAGGAUGAGUUUUAACAUUUAUGAGUUAACUUCAUCCACAUCAGUAAAUUUGACAAGUAUUUUUGAAGACCCAUCUUUGGGUUUUAUUAAAUAGAAAUUUCUGAAAGUUGUAUGCCCAAGGGUAUUUUGUUUUUCUCAUGUGUGUUCAAAUUUGGGAAGAAUGAAUUUUGCCUCCUAUUCACUCGGUAGGAGAUUUAGUGUCUCCUUCUGAAUUAGCCCUUUCUGUUCCUGAAGGAAAGUAUUUAUGAAAAAUCAGACUCCAUUCUGGAAACUGAAUGAUUUUUGUAUUUUGCUGCAGUUAGAUGGAGUCCUAUAAAUGAGCCCAAAACAUGCUGGCUAAAUCUCUCAUAAAAGGCAAAUAUCACAAAGAGGAAUGGCCCAAGUCUUAUUUUGGCCCCUGGCCUGUGUUUGUCUAAAAAGACUUUUAGAAGUGUCACAAAACACUAAAGCACUGCCUAAAUCAUCCCUUCCUAACUUUUUGCUUAUGGGGGUGCAAGGGAAGUUGCACGUGGUGGGUGGGGGUGCUGAGAGAGAGAGAGAGAGAACACAAAGGGCCAGCUCCCACUUGGAGCUCCCCUCGUUUCUCUCCAUUUUGCUCUUCAGGAUGUCCCCACCCCACUCUGCAUUCUCACCACACCCACACAUGAACCCAGCAUCUGCCCAGGUGCCACGAAUCAUAUUACAACUUUGCUCCCUGGCAGAGAGUGGCCAGAGAGAAGUUUCUGGAGGUGAGGAAGUGAGCCUGCCUGACUGCUUUGGUGGCAGAAACCAGGGGCUUAACCAGUGACUCUGUGCUCGAGGCUUGUUUGUGAAAUCCUUUAGCAACUCUUCAGAAGCCUCUCCUCUCUGACUUCUCAGAGAUGCUGGCUCUUCUACUUUGGGAAGUUCCUUUGCUAGUAACACAUUUGAGGUGAGUUAAAUGUCUUCCUCCUUCAGCCUCAGCUUCCUGUGCCUAAGGGUGAGUUAAGCAAUUAGUCCUAAAUAGCCCCAGCUGUUAGGGUUUCUCCAGAGGAUGCUCCUUGUGACUUUGAUUGCUUCUAAUGAGGCUAUUGGCUUUAUCUGUAAUAGACAAUGUUAGAUUACACAUCUAUGUCUUUUACAGCACCUUUUACCCCCAGGGCUUUACGUUUUCUGAGACCACUCUUGAGAACCUUGGAUCCAGUGGCAUUUUUCUUCUUGUGAAUAAAAAAUUAUUAUCUUUCCUGUUCUCCCUGUGAGAUCAGCCUUGUUCUUGUUCUGCUCUGGGGUACUCUGUAUUUAGGGAAAUUACUCAUGACUCUCGGGUACUGAAAAGACACACACACACACACACACACACACACACACACACCAUGCACAGGGGAAUGGGAGAGCAAGAACGUGUGAGAGAGAGCCACUUGAAGAGAGACAGGGAGAAAGAAAGAGAGUAGGAGAAAGCAAUAAAGAAAGCGAGAUCACAGUCAGGCCUGAGAAGGUGACAGCAAGCCAGUGUUUUAGAGGUAGGGAAAGAGCCCAAGAUGGAUGGAGAAAGCUCAUGCAGGAGCAAGAGAGCACACAUGGGAGUGCCAGCAACCUUGAAAAAAAGCACCAGUGACAGCAAAGGGAAUCUAUGAGGCCAGGAGGCUGGGCGAGCAAAAGCAAGAGAGUGCAAGAGAUCAAGAAAGGGGGAAAGGAGGUGGGAGAGGGAGAGCGAGCCUUCAGGGCAAAGGAGUCAAUGAGAGAGAUCAGCACAUUAUUUGUGGGCAGAUGAAGAGAAAGUCUAAAUGAGGAGCUGCUUUCCCCUCAUCUUGUUGAGUUGGUGGAAGAGGAAGAGAAGAUGCACAGGGCACAGACUCCAGCUUUCAUUAAUCCAAAAUGGAAUUUCUGGGACAUACAUGCUCAGGAUCAAUGUCAUCUUUAAAGACCCAGAUUCCAAUUAGAACCACAAGUACACCUCCCCAUCCUUCAGUAUUAUUUGAAAUUUUAGAACAACUGCCAUUAUUCUACACAAAGUAAAGGAUGAUCAUUUUGGAGUAUGUUUUUAUCAAACCACCUCCCUAUCCACAGACCUGUGUUAGACAGCUUACCUUAGUGGUUGCCAAACACCAGAAGUAGAUCAUUGUCAUGAUUUUGGAGGGCUGGGCCGAGGCCUGGAAUUCUAUGGCUUUAAUACGUGGCUCCAUUGGGAGAUUCCAUUGCCCAGGAAGACACUGGCCUUAAGCUACACCCUUUUUCAGAAAGCAGUAACAAAUUCAGUUGGACCACUGACCUGAAGCCAGAUUGCUUUCCAACAAGGCCCAAACUAAAGGGGGUACCAAAAAAUCAGUAAUCAACAUAAAUAACAUUUUAAUGAUAUGAUUUUUUAAAAGAGAAGUUUCUACUUAUGUUGCCCAGGCUGGAGUGCAGUGUCUAUUCAUAGGCGCGAUCAUGGAACUCUUGAGCUCAAGUGAUCCUCCUGCCUUGGUUUCCUGAGUAGCUGUAAUGAUAUGUUUUAAAGACUUAAAAUUAAUGUAGACAAAUCCAAAAUGAACAAAUAUCAAAAUUUUAAAUACAGUUUCCAACUCUGCCCUUGCACACCCCUGCCUCUCUUGACCCACCCUAACACCAUCCUUGGUUCCAGUUAAACUUUAUAUACAGAAUCAGGCAGCCAUCCUGUGGGCCAUAUUUUCUUGACUUAAAAAAAAAAAACCAUUGCCUUAAAUAUCAUUUAUUCAAGUAGAAUCCAAAUCUUGUUUGUUUUCUAAUACUGUUUUUCAAUAAAAGCAACCAGGGCUCCUUGGAGAAAUGACCGAUUCCAGGACUGAGGCAGAAAAUACACAAGAUAAGCCUGGAACAUCUUGUAUUGCCAGAAAGUAAGGAAGUGUUAACAAAUACACAAACAAAAACAAAAAGCAGAACAUCACAGGAGCCAACUAAAAGAGCUACCAACAGCCAAAGGUAUAAAAACUUGAGAAAAUAUACUAGUAUUAUUGGACUAUAACCCAAAGUAUAAAAUAAACAUCCAAGAGUCCAUACUGAUAUAAUUAAAUGGUUAAAUAAAUGGAUGAUAGACACAUCUUUUGUGCAGGGUAAUUCCAAAUAAUUUGUGUAGAUUCUCUGCCCUCAAGGAGGUGGAGUGUAACUCCUCACUCCUUAAGUAUGAACUGCGAAUAGUGACUUCCUUGUAAAAGAGUAUAGUAUGGGCCAGGCAUGGUGCCGCAUGCCGGAAAUCCCAGCACUUUAGGAGGUUGAGGCAGGAGGAUUGCUUGAGACCAGGAGUUUGAGACCAGCCUGGGCAACAUAGUGAGACUCCCUCUCUACAAAAAAAUUAAAAA